GACAGUCCACCAAAAGAUGUCAAACCAAAUCCAGCCUAUUGUAAAGCUCUGGGACCUCCCUUCCAAGGACACCGAACACAAGCUUAGACACCGCUGCGAAAAGCUGUCCAAAAGCGCCUGGCCGGACAGAAAUGUAAGGAGCCCAGGCCAAAACGAAUUAGAACCCCCAACAGAGGGUCCCGCAGACACCGCGGAAAAGAAGGUGGCAUUUAUUCCGGGGUAGACAGCUACGAACCAGUUACCCCAGCCAGUCUCUGGGGGCUCUCCAACCCAAGUUCAGGUUUAUGGCAGAUAUAUUGGUUGGGUGCCUUCCCCUACAAACAUCACAGCCCGCCUCCGGGGCCCACCGCCGCUCACAGAGAAGACCCCUCAGCUUCACAUCCGUUCCUUUUGCCCUCGGACAAAGGCAGAGGAGCUGUGGAGCUGACCCAGCGCUGUGGGGCAGUAAAAAUGCCUUGUUCGGGCCACCCAUCUUUGGGCCCGGCUUCAUCUGCGAUGUCAGCACCAAAGGUUUUUUUUUUUUUUUUCCUGGUUUUGUUUUGUUUUUACAACGCAUCCUGGGCGGGUGUAUGCAUUUGGUGGUAGUGGGGUGGGGGGAACCGAACAGAGGAGGGGUUGGCAGUGAAGCCUGGGUUAUAGAACUCUCCUUCCUCUCCCUCCUUCCAGGGUUGCCGUGCAGGGAGUGUCAGCCACGUCUAGCGCACAGUCCCAGGCCCCAGGGCGAAGGCGGCCAGGGGAAAUGGGGCUCAGGGAUUGCUAAGCAAACGCAUCACUGGUGGUCUCCAGCGCCUGCGGAGGUAGGAUCGCCUCUUUUCUUAAGGGGCGUGUUAUUUUGUUCUCUUUUGAAAGUAGGAGGGGGUUCAUUCGUUUCUCGCUGCGGGGGGUGGGAGAGAACGUUGCUGCACCGCCUGGGUCUCCAAGAGGGAGGGUGCGGGGAUGUCUGCAAUGGUACUAUAAUUAUUCCUGGGCUGAGAGAGCAAGUAAAGGGGACGGGGCGAGCGUCACCUGGAGCUGUGGCAGUGGCAGCAGGGAAGGUCGCGAGGGGCUUACCCGGGCGGGCGGGCGCUGUCCUGCCGCAGGUGAGGGAGGGCGCAGGCUGGCGGGAGGGAGGGCGCGCGCGAGACAGGCGCGAGGAAGGGGGGAGGGGAGGAGGGCGCGCGCGCGCACACCUGUCCUGGACAGCGGCGCUAGCCGAGCUGCGCCUCACUUAGGCUCUGCGGGCUGAGGAGGAAGGAGGGCGGGCUGGCGGGCGGGGGCGGGACGCCGAGGGGAGGAGGAGGAGGCGGCUCGGAUGGCUGGCUCGGCUCUCGCUCGCUCUCCCUCCCAUGGGCAAGUCCGGCUCACACCCUGCUUCUCCCGCUCACUCACAGCCCCCUUGGCUCUCCCUCCUCCUCCUCCUUCCCCUGCGGGAUCCGCUCGCCGCCGCCGCCGCCGCCGCAGACGGCAAGUCGUGGCAGCCAGACGUCGGCGCGUAACCCGGCGCUCCGCAGUGCCUGAUGGCUGAGAAGAAUCGCAGAGGACUAGAAAAGGUUUGAGUCUGAAAUUAUCUGGCACAGAGGAUUAAAGCUCAGAAAUAAGUGAUUGCGAAACAGUUCAACUUCCCUGUUAAUGACAACAACAACAGCAACACGCUUAUUAAUUCCUAGCUGGAGUUUUUCCUAAUUAACAGCAUCAAGCUUAUGAAGAUUUCCAAGACUUUAUUGUUGACCCUUGUUGAAGAGAACUCUACUUGGCUUCUUUCCUGGCUUUCCUAAAUUGUUCACAUACAAGAUAAACUACCGUCAUUCAGACUUACAGAAGUGAGAAGACAAGCUGAACCAAAUGUAAAAUGGUAGCAAUUUACAGAUGUCAGAACUAACAUGUGGAUGAACUUAGAGAUGGAGAAGAAAGCUGGGCUUUUCCAAAGAGUGGAUCUAUCUGAACUGGAUAGCACUAUUGAACUUUGUUGCAUAUUUUGUGGUAGCUCUAAAACUCCUCUGCUUGCUUACAUACAACCAGACACCAGUGCCUUCUGAAGCUAAUCCAGGCCAUUUUUAUAACCUAAUGCAGUAGCACUUUGCAAUUAGAUGAAGAAGAUCGGUGGGAUUUCUUUCUGUGGUGAUUAAAAUGUGUCAGGGGAAGAAAUCAAGACAAUACUCCAAGUGAAAAAUAUAAAGUCAGUUAUUUCUUUAAUAUUUUGUGUUAUAGUAAUCAUUUUUAUAUUUUGAGCAUACUUUUUCUUGUCUACUUAAAUACUCAAAAUUAAUUAUAAAAUGUAAAUGUAAGCACAAUGAGAUACCAUCUCAUCCCAGUUAAAAUGGCUUUUAUCAAAAAGAUAGGGAAUAAUGAAUACUGGUGGAAGGAUGUGGAGAAUGGGGAACCCUCGUACACUGUCAAUGAGAAUGUAAAUUAGUACAGCCACUAUGGAAAACUGUAUGGAAGUGCCUCCGAAAACAAAGUAGAACUACCAUGUGAUCCAGCAAUUACACUAGUGGGUAUAUAUUCAAAAGAAAGGAAAUCAACAUAUUAAAGAGAUAGCUGCAUUCUCAUGUUUAUUGAAGUCCUGUUGAAAUAGCCAAAAUAUGGAAUCAACCUAAGUGCCCAUCAGUGGAUGAAUGGUUAAAGAAAAUGUGAUUGAUAUGCAAUGGAAUAUUAUUCAGCCAUAAAAAAGAAUGAAAUCCUGGCGGGGCACAGUGGCUCAUGCAAGUAAUCCCAGCACUGACCUCAUGAAGACAGAGAGUAGAUUGGUGGUUACCAGAGGUUGAGAAGGGGAGAGGAGAGGAGGGAUGAAGAGAGGUUGAUUGAUGGAUAGAAAUAUACAGUUUGAUAAUGAUAAAUCAGUAGGGUGACUAUAGUUUAUAAUAACCUAUUGUAUGGUUCAAAAUAGCUAAAAGAGAAUAAUUGAAAUAACGUAAGACAAAAAUUUAAGAUGAUAGAUAUCCCAAUUACACUGAUUUGAUCUUUACAAAUUAUAUGAAUGUAUUAAAUUAUUACAUGUAUCCCCAAAAUAUGUACAAGUAUUUUGUAUCAAUAAAAAAUAAAAUUUAAGAUAAAGUAAAUGUAAUGAUUAGCUUAUAUUUCCUAGAUCGGAAAUAAAUAUUUACUUAAGUA